GCCUCCCGCCAGCCUCCCCGCUCCGCCAUGUUCGCCUUCUGGCCCACUCACAGGAGAGUCGCCUUUCAGGCGUGGCCGCAGUCACUCGCCCGCCGCCGAACCCCGCCAGGAGAGGAAAGCACCAGCAGGCAGCUGGCUCCGGUUUUGGGGUAUCUGGGCUCCAGGCAGAAGCACAGCCUCCCCGACCUGCCCUACGACUACGGCGCCCUGGAACCUCACAUCAACGCGCAGAUCAUGCAGCUGCACCACAGCAAGCACCACGCGGCCUACGUGAACAACCUGAACGUCACCGAGGAGAAGUACCAGGAGGCGUUGGCCAAGGGAGAUGUUACAGCCCAGAUAGCUCUUCAGCCUGCACUGAAGUUCAAUGGUGGUGGUCAUAUCAAUCAUAGCAUUUUCUGGACAAACCUCAGCCCUAACGGUGGUGGAGAACCCAAAGGGGAGUUGCUGGAAGCCAUCAAACGUGACUUUGGUUCCUUUGACAAGUUUAAGGAGAAGCUGACGGCUGCAUCUGUUGGUGUCCAAGGCUCAGGUUGGGGUUGGCUUGGUUUCAAUAAGGAACGGGGACACUUACAAAUUGCUGCUUGUCCAAAUCAGGAUCCACUGCAAGGAACAACAGGCCUUAUUCCACUGCUGGGGAUUGAUGUGUGGGAGCACGCUUACUACCUUCAGUAUAAAAAUGUCAGGCCUGAUUAUCUAAAAGCUAUUUGGAAUGUAAUCAACUGGGAGAAUGUAACUGAAAGAUACAUGGCUUGCAAAAAGUAAACCACGAUCGUUAUGCUGAGUAUGUUAAGCUCUUUAUGACUGUUUUUGUAGUGGUAUAGAGUACUGCAGAAUACAGUAAGCUGCUCUAUUGUAGCAUUUCUUGAUGUUGCUUAGUCACUUAUUUCAUAAACAACUUAAUGUUCUGAAUAAUUUCUUACUAAACAUUUUGUUAUUGGGCAAGUGAUUGAAAAUAGUAAAUGCUUUGUGUGAUUGAAUCUGAUUGGACAUUUUCUUCAGAGAGCUAAAUUACAAUUGUCAUUUAUAAAACCAUCAAAAAUAUUCCAUCCAUAUACUUUGGGGACUUGUAGGGAUGCCUUUCUAGUCCUAUUCUAUUGCAGUUAUAGAAAAUCUAGUCUUUUGCCCCAGUUACUUAAAAAUAAAAUAUUAACACUUUCCCAAGGGAAACACUCGGCUUUCUAUAGAAAAUUGCACUUUUUGUCGAGUAAUCCUCUGCAGUGAUACUUCUGGUAGAUGUCACCCAGUGGUUUUUGUUAGGUCAAAUGUUCCUGUAUAGUUUUUGCAAAUAGAGCUGUAUACUGUUUAAAUGUAGCAGGUGAACUGAACUGGGGUUUGCUCACCUGCACAGUAAAGGCAAACUUCAACAGCAAAACUGCAAAAAGGUGGUUUUUGCAGUAGGAGAAAGGAGGAUGUUUAUUUGCAGGGCGCCAAGCAAGGAGAAUUGGGCAGCUCAUGCUUGAGACCCAAUCUCCAUGAUGACCUACAAGCUAGAGUAUUUAAAGGCAGUGGUAAAUUUCAGGAAAGCAGAAGUUAAAGGCAAAAUUGUAAAUCAGUCGAGAUCGGGUGCCUUCAGGGUGGUAUGGCUGUAUACCAAAAUUGUAAAUCACUACAUGAAGCUUAUAUAUUGGUUUGGCCUGAAAGGUGAAGUGGGGUAGGCAGGGGGCGGGCUUACAGGUUAUGGUGGAUUCAAAGACUCCCUGAUUUGUGAUUGGUUAAGGAAGCAAAGCUUUGUCUAAAAACUUGGGGUCCGCAGAAAGGAACAUUAAGGUCUGGCCAGGCCCCUCAGGAAGAAACUGAGAGCAAAGAAUGGAGGUCAGAGUUUAGUCCCUGGUGUUCCCCCUUAUCUGACGUCUGUGUGAAUCCAUUUGGUGGGGGUCUGGGUUUCUGAAAAGUAGCUCAGGGGCACGUGUUAAGGAUGUCUCUAGGUGACUCUAACUUCCCUGGCUAUUGUUUGAAACUGUUAUGACCUUCUUGCUUAUCAGCUUGCUGGUUUCCUUCUCGGGGCGAGCUGGGUGCCUGGAGUUUUCGGUGAAGGAAACUCAAGAUUCUCCUUUAUUUCUGUGCUUGUGGGAAUCCCCCUGGCACACCCCAAAGAGGGGUCCCUGCUCCGUCUCACAGGGAUCUUUUUGUAUAUUUGGCUUAGCAUCAUACAUUUGCCAUGUUGUUUCAUCAUCUGCCUAAUUUACUGUUUUUGAAUAUUUCAUUUGUUUCUAAUUGUUACUACAGAUAAUGCUGGGGUGAGCAACUCUGUGUACAUAGGUUUAUCUCCUAUUGGAAUAUUUUCUUUAUAUAGGCGUUUUUUUUUUUUCUUUUUUUUUGGAGACAGAGUCUUGCUCUGUUGCCCAGGCUGGAGUGCAGUGGCGCGACCGGAGCUCACUGCAACCUCCACUUCCCGGGUUCAAGUGAUUGUCCCACCUCAGCCUCCUGAAUAGCUGGGAUUACAGGUGCAUGCUACCAUGCCUGGCUACUUUUUGUAUUUUUAGCAGAGACAGGGUUUCACCAUGUUGGCCAGGGUGGUCUCGAACUCCUGACCUCAAGUGAUCCGUCUGGCUCAGCCUCCCAAAGUGCUGGGAUUACAGGUGUGAGCCACUGCACCUGGCCUAUAUAGGCUUUUUUCUUAAACCUAUUUAGUAAUGUUUUCCCAAGUUUAUUUUUUAUUUUUAAUUUUUUCCCCAAGUUUAUUUUUCUAUUUUUUUUUCAUGGAAAAAUGGGGUAACUUAGCAGUUUCAAUAUUGAAGACUGAAGUUUAAAAAAAAUUUAAAUUCAAGGUACUUUUAAAAUUCAGUUAGAAAAGUAGGCUUUAAAAAUUAUUAGAGACAAGAGUACCAAAGCGGUGUGUGUAUGUGUGUGUGUGUAUGCAUGCUUGUGGAUUGGAAAAACUUUGGAGACUGAUUACUUUUCAUUAUAUAUGUGUCACAGUGAAACAGCUUUUAUGUGUCAUGUAAGAUUACUGCUUGCCUCUCUAAGGAAGGUCGUGACUGUUUAAAUAGACGGGCAAGGUGGAACCUUUUGAAAGAUGAGCUUUUGAAUAUAAGUUGUCUGCUAGAUCAUGGUUUGUAUUGAACUAACAAGGUUUGCAGAUCUGCUGACUUAUAUAAAGCUUUUUGAUUCCUACUAAGCUUUAAGAUUUAAAAAAUGUUCAAUGUUGAAAUUUCUGUGGGGCUCUAUUUUUGCUUUGGCUUUCUGGUGAGAGAGUGAGGAAGCAUUCUUUCCUUCACUAAGUUUGUCUUUCUUGUCUUCUGGAUAGAUUGAUUUUAAGAGACUAAGGGAAUUUACAAACUAAAGAUUUUAGUCAUCUGGUGGAAAAGGAGACUUUAAGAUUGUUUAGGGCUGGGCGGGGUGACUCACAUCUGUAAUCCCAGCACUUUGGGAGGCCAAGGCAGGCAGAACACUUGAAGGAGUUCAAGACCAGCGUGGCCAACGUGGUGAAACCCUGUCUCUACUAAAAAUACAAAAAUUGUUUAGCUCUGUUUUUCAUAAUAGAAAUAGAAAAGGUAAAAUUGCUUUUCUUCUGAAAAGAACAAGUAUUGUUCAUCCAAGAAGGGUUUUUGUGACUGAAUCAGCAGUGCCUGCCCUAGUCAUAGCUGUGCUUCAAAAACCUCAGCAUGAUUAGUGUUGGAGCAAAACAAGGAAGCAAAGCAAAUACUGUUUUUGAAAUUCUAUCUGUUGCUUGAACUAUUUUGUAAUAAUUAAACUUUGAUGUUGAGAAAUCACAACUUUAUUGUACACUUCAUUGCAACUUGAAAUUCAUGGUCUUAAAGUGAGAUUUGAAUUUCUAUUGAGCGCCUUUAAAAAAGUAAUACCAAACCAUAAAGUUAAAAUCUAUGUAUAUUGAGUCAUAUCUAAAACCACGUAUAAACAUAAAUUGUAUUUCCUGUUUUAAUUCCAGGGGAAGUACUGUUUGGGAAAGCUAUUAUUAGGUAAAUGUUUUACAAAUUACUGUUUCUCACUUUCAGUCAUACCCUAAUGAUCCCAGCAAGAUAAUGUCCUGUCUUCUAAGAUGUGCAUCAAGCCUGGUACAUACUGAAAACCCUAUAAGGUCCUGGAUAAUUUUUGUUUGAUUAUUCAUUGAAGAAACAUUUAUUUUCCAAUUGUGUGAAGUUUUUGACUGUUAAUAAAAGAAUCUGUCAACCAUCAAAGAGGUCUGCAUUAUGCUUGCAUGUCAAAAACUUUAAAAAUCCUAUAAUCUUCUGUCAUUUUCACUGAGUUUCCAUGGGAAAGGAAUAGUAAAUAAUGGGUAGUUGAAAUAUUACUCUUAAGACCAAGACCUGUAUCUCCAGUCAUAUCUGUAAUAACAUCAUCUGAUAACCUAAAAGCAUAGUAUUAGGGAUAUACGACAAAACCAAAGUGUUUUUGCUGUUGUCACAUACCACUCAAUACUUUUACACCAGGUUGUCCAGUGGACACCAGCUGGAUGUCCUAUAAUUCAAUUCUGACACUGUCUACCUGGAAUUGGAGUCAGAUCCCACAGGUGGAGGGCUCAGCCCACAAGACUGCCCCCACUCCAGAUACCAAUCGCAAGUCCCUAUACUUCUGACUGGCUAUAAAGUGGGGUUCCCGUGACCCUUUCCUUGGUUUUGAUUUAUUUGCUAGAGCAGCUCCCAGAACACAGAGAAACACUCUACUUAUGUUUACCCAUUUUUAAUUUUAUUACUUUAUUAAAACUACAUAUUGGUUACAAUACUAAUUUAUUGUAAAGGAUAUUUCAUUUAUUUAUUUUUUUAUUUAGAGAUGGAGUCUCACUGUGUCACCCAGGCUGGAGUGCGGUGGCACAGUCUCAACUCACUGCAACCUCCACCUCCUGAGUUCAAGCGAUUCUCAUGCCUCAGCCUCCCAAGUAGCUGGGAUUACAAGUGUGCACCACCAUGCCCAGCUAAUUUUUGUAUUUUUAGUAGAGAUGGGGUUUCACUCUGUUGGCCAGGCUGGUCUCAAACUCCUGACCUCAAGUCAUCCACCCACCUCAGCCUCCCAAAGUGCUGAGAUUACAGGUGUGAGCCAUUGCCUCUGGCUUGUAAAGGAUAUUUCAAAGAAUACAGAUGAACAGCCAGAUGGAAGAGAUGCACAGGGCAAGGCAUGUGGGAAGGGGUAUGGAGCUUUCAUGCUCUCUCCACGUCAUCAGCUACCCAGAAGCUCAUCUGGACCCCGACCCUUUGGGGUUUUACGGAGGCUUCAUUAUGUCAGCAUUACCAUUGGCAAUUGGCGAUUAACUCAACCUUCAGCCUCUCUCCCCUUUCUGGAGGUUGGGGGUUGAGGCUGGGAGUCCAAACCCUCCAAUCUUGCCUUGGUCUUUCUGGUAAGCAGCCCCCCGUCCUGAAGCUACCUAGAGGCUCCCAGCCACCAAUCAUUUCAUUGGCAAACCAAAGAUACUUCAAGGGGUUUAGGAGCCAAGAGACCAAGCAAGGAUUGAGACAAUAUAUAUAUUUCUUAUAAAUAACAUGAUCACAAAUAGUAUUUUAUAUAUUUCUCAUAAUAGCUGGUUGUGGUUACUCACACCUAUCAUCCCAGCUACUAAGAAGCUAAGGCAGGAGGAUCACAGGCCCAGGAGUUUGCAGCUGUAGUGAGCUAUGAUUGUGCUACUGCACUCCAGCCUGGGUGACAGUGUGAGACCCUGUCUCUUAAAGUUCUUGUAACAUCUUAGAACAUUAACCAACCACAGAUUAUUGCCUUAACUCUGAAAAAUAAAGUAAUCAUACUUUUACAAGAUGUAUUUUACAUAAAGUUCUGGUGAUAUUUUACUCUGGUCAUUGGAAUAUAGGAGCUUACCACCUGGUACCACUCUUCCUAAAGUGGUAUACUAUUUGGUAUAGUACUGGCAUACUAUUUGGAAAGGGAUGUGAAGUUGGCAUGACCUGUCUAGGGUGAAGUCAUGCUGUCUGCUAUUCAUUGUGGGCUUUACAGUAAUGAGAGUGCUUCUGUUGUCAAGAUGCUUCUGGGACACGUUAAAAAAAAUUUAAGAUUUCUCAGUUUGUGAAAAGGAAGGAGCACGAAUGCUUUCAAGUUCCUAUGACAUGCUAGUCAUCUUUCAGUGUGUCCCAUUGUUGCACCCAGUAGUCUCGAUGCCCAGCGUCACGGUGAUUCCAAGUUUGCCUCUCUGCCCACUAUAAUUUGUGCUCCAUGAAGUCCCAGGACAUGAGGUUCUUGUUCAUUUGUGCGUCUGGGCCCAUAUCCAAAUAUUAAACAAUGUGACUUAAUGUAUUUAUCAUAUUGUAAAUAUGGGUAUCCCCAAGGCUCAGAAGUUAACACAGCAUAUCCACAGAGAGGUUUGACAGCAUGGCUGUGGUGACUGGGAAGGCCUUAUGCUUGCUCCUCCUUCUGCUGCUUGCCUUUGUGUGGGCAUGGAAAGAACAUUGAAUUAGGUACUGGAAGACCUGGGUCCUGGUCUUGGAGAUUUUACCAGAGCACCUGUGGGAUAUUGGUCAAGAUGCCUGGUUUUAGUCCUGCUCCUUUGCUGUGAAAGAGGAUCUUAAGGUGCCAACUCUGGCAUUUUAUUUUUUACUUAUUUAUUUUUAAAUUAUACUUUAAGUUCUAGGGUACAUGUGUACAACAUGCAGGUUUGUUACAUGUAUACAUGUGCCAUGUUGGUGUGCUGCACCUAUUAACUCGUCAUUUACAUUAGGUAUAUCUCCUAAUGCUAUCCCUCCCCCUUCUCCCCACCCCUCGACAGGCCCCGGUGUGUGAUGUUCCCCUUCCUGUGUCCAAGUGUUCUCAUUGUUCAAUUCCCAUCUAUGAGUGAGAACAUGCGGUGUUUGUUUUUUUGUCCUUGGAAUAGUUUGCUGAGAAGGAUGGUUUCCAGCUUCAUCCAUGUCCCUAUAAAGGACAUGAACUCUUCCUUUUUUAUGGCUGCAUAGUAUUCCAUGGUGUAUAUGUGCCACAUCUUCUUAAACCAAUCUAUCAUUGAUGGACAUUUGGGUUGGUUCCAAGUCUUUGCUAUUGUGAACAGUGCCACAAUAAAUAUACGUGUGCAUGUGUCUUUAUAGCAGCAUGAUUUAUAAUCCUUUGGGUAUAUACCCAGUAAUGGGAUGGCUGGGUCAAAUGGUAUUUCUAGUUCUAGAUCCCUGAGGAAUCGCCACACUGUCUUCCACAAUGGUUGAACUAGUUUACAGUCCCACCACCAGUGUAAAAGUGUUCCUAUUUCUCCACAUCCUCUCCAGCACCUGUUGUUUCCUGACUUUUUAAUGAUUGACAUUCUAACUGGUGUGAGAUGGUAUCUCAUUGUGGUUUUGAUUUGCAUUUCUCUGAUGGCCCAUGAUGAUGAGCAUUUUUUUCAUGUGUCUGUUGGAUGCAUGGAUGUCUUCUUUUGAGAAGUGUCUCUUCAUAUCCUUCACCUACUUUUUGAUGGGGUUUGUUUUUUUCUUGUAAGUUUGUUUGAGUUCCUUGUAGAUUCUGGAUAUUAGCCCUUUGUCAGAUGAGUAGAUUGCAAAAAUUUUCUCCCAUUUUGUAGGUUGCCUGUUCACUCUGAUGGUAGUUUCUUUUGCUGUGCAGAAGCUCUUGAGUUUAAUGAGAUCCCAUUUGUCAAUUUUGGCUUCUGUUGCCAUUGCUUUUGGUGUUUUAGACAUGAAGUCCUUGCCCAUGCCUGUGUCCUGAAUGGUACUGCAUAGGUUUUCUUCUAGGGUUUUUAUGGUUUUAGGUCUAACAUUUAAGUCUUUAAUCCAUCUUGAAUUAAUUUUUGUAUAAGGUGUAAGGAAGGGAUCCAGUUUCAGCUUUCUACAUGUGGCUAGCCAGUUUUCCCAGCACCAUUUAUUAAAUAGGGAAUCCUUUCCCCAUUUCUUGUUUUUGUCAGGUUUCUCAAAGAUCAGAUAGUUGUAGAUGUGUGGUAUUAUUUCUGAGGGCUCUGUUCUGUUCCAUUGGUCUAUAUCUCUGUUUUGGUACUAGUACCAUGCUGUUUUGGUUACUGCAGCCUUGUAGUAUAGUUUGAAAUCAGGUAGCGUGAUGCCUCCAGCUUUGUUCUUUUGGCUUAGGAUCGUUUUGGCAGUGCAGGCUCUUUUUUGGUUCCACAUGAACUUUAAAGUAGUUUUUUCCAAUUCUAUGAAGAAAGUCAUGGGUAGCUUGAUGGGGAUGGCAUUGAAUCUAUAAAUUACCUUGGGCAGUAUAGCCAUUUUCACGAUAUUGAUUCUUCCUAUCCAUGAGCAUGGAAUGUUCUUCCAUUUGUUUGUGUCCUCUUUUAUUUCCUUGAGCAGUGGUUUGUAGUUCUCCUUGAAGAGGUCCUUCACAUCCCUUGUAAGUUGGAUUCCUAGGUAUUUUAUUCUCUUUGAGGCAGUUGUGAAUGGGAGUUCACUCAUGAUUUGGCUCUCUGUUUGUCUGUUGUUGGUGUAUAAGAAUGCUUGUGAUUUUUGCACAUUGAUUUUGUAUCCUGAGAUUUUGCUGAAGUUGCUUAUCAAAUUAAGGAGAUUUUGGGCUGAGAUGAUGGGGUUUUCUAAAUAUAAAAUCAUGUCAUCUGCAAACAGGGACAAUUUGACUUCCUCUUUUCCUUAUUGAAUACCCUUUAUUUCUUUCUCCUGCCUGAUGGCCCUGGCCAGAACUUCCAACACUAUGUUGAAUAGGAGUGGUGAGAGAGGGCAUCCCUGUCUUGUGCCAGUUUUCAAAGGGAAUGCUUCCAGUUUUUGCCCAUUCAGUCUGAUAUUGGCUGUGGGUUUGUCAUAGAUAGCUCUUAUUAUUUUGAGAUAUGUCCCAUCAAUACCUAAUUCAUUGAGAGUUUUUAGCAUGAAGGGCUGUUGAAUUUUGUCCAAGGCCUUUUCUGCAUCUGUUGAGAUAAUCAUGUGGUUUUUGUCUUUGGUUCUGUUUAUAUGCUGGAUUACUUUUAUUGAUUUGUGUAUGUUGAACCAGCCUUGCAUCCCAGGGAUGAAGCCCACUUGAUCAUGGUGGAUAAGCUUUUUGAUAUGCUGCUGGAUUCAGUUUGCCAGUAUUUUAUUGAGGAUUUUUGCAUUGAUUUUCAUCAGGGAUAUUGGUCUAAAGUUCUCUUUUUUUGUUAUGUCUCUGCCAGGCUUUGGUAUCAGGAUGAUGCUGGCUUCAUAAAAUGAGUUAGGGAGGAUUCCCUCUUUUUCUAUUGAUUGGAAUAGUUUCAGAAGGAAUGGUACCAGCUCUUCCUUGUACCUCUGGUAGAAUUCGGCUGUGAAUCCAUCUUGUCCUGGACUUUUUUUGGUUGGUAGGCUAUUAAUUAUUGCCUCAAUUUCAGAGCCUGUUAUUGGUCUAUUCAGGGAUUAAACUUCUUCCUGGUUUAGUUUUGAGAGGGUGUAUGUGUCCAGGAAUUUAUCUAUUUCUUCUAGAUUUUCUAGUUUAUUUGCAUAGAGGUGUUUAUAGUAUUCUCUGUGUACUCUGUAUUUCUGUGGGAUUGGUGGUGAUAUCCACUUUAUCAUUUUUUAUUGCAUUUAUUUGAUUCUUCUCUCUUUUCUUGUUUAUUAGUCUUGCUAGCGGUCUAUCAAUUGUGUUUAUCUUUUCAAAAAACCAGCUCCUGGAUUCAUUCAUUUUUUGAAGGUUUUUUUGUGUCUCUGUCUCCUUCAGUUCUGCUCUGAUCUUAGUUAUUUCUUGUCUUCUGCUAGCUGUUGAAUGUGUUUGCUCUUGCUUCUCUAAUAUUUUUAAUUGUGAUGUUAGAGUGUCAAUUUUAGAUCUUUCCUGCUUUCUCUUGUGGGCACUUAGUGCUGUAAAUUUCCCUCUACACACUGCUUUAAAUGUGUCCCAGAGAUUCUGGUAUGUUGUGUCUUUGUUCUCGUUGGUUUCAAAGAACAUCUUUAUUUCUGCCUUCAUUUUGUUAUGUACCCAGUAGUCAUUCAGGAGCAGGUUGUUCAGUUUCCAUGUAGCUGAGUGGUUUUGAGUGAGUUUCUUAAUCCUGAGUUCUAGUUUGAUUGCACUGUGGUCUGAGACAGUAUGUUAUAAUUUCUGUUCUUUUACAUUUGCUGAGGAGUGCUUUACUUCCAACUAUGUGGUCAAUUUUGGAAUAGGUGCGAUGUGGUGCUGAGAAGAAUGUAUAUUCUGUUGAUUUGGGGUGGAGAGUUCUGUAGAUGUCUAUUAGGUCUGCUUGGUGCAGAGCUGAAUUCAAUUCCUGGAUAUCCUUGUUAACUUUCUGUCUCGUUGAUCUGUCUAAUAUUGACAGUGGGGUGUUAGAGUCUCCCAUUGUUAUUGUGUGGGAGUCUAAAUCUCUUUGUAGGUCUCUAAGGACUUGGUUUAUGAAUCUGGGUGCUCCUGUAUUGGGUGCAUAUAUAUUUAAGAUAGUUAGCUCUUCUUGUUGAAUUGAUCCCUUUACUAUCAUGUAAUGGCCUUCUUUGUCUCUUUUGAUCUUUGUUGGUUUAAAGUCUGUUUUAUCAGAGACUAGGAUUGCAACCCCGGCCUUUUUUUUUGUUUUCCGUUUGCUUGGUAGAUCUUCCUCCAUCCUUUUAUUUUGAGCCUAUGUGUGUGUGUCUCUGUACGUGAGAUGGGUUUCCUGAAUACAGCACCCUGAUGGGUCUUGACUCUUUAUCCAGUGUGCCAGUCUGUGUCUUUUAAUUGGAGCAUUUAGCCCAUUUACAUUUAAGGUUAAUAUUGUUAUGUGUGAAUUUGAUCCUGUCACUAGGAUGUUCACUGGUUAUUUUGCUCGUUAGUUGAUGCAGUUUCUUCCUAGCCUCAAUGGUCUUUACAAUUUGGCAUGUUUUUGCAGUGGCUGAUACUGGUUGUUCCAUUCCAUGUUUAGUGCUUCCUUCAGGAGCUCUUGUAAGGCAGGCCUGGUGGUGACAAAAUCUCUCAGCAUUUGCUUGUUUGUAAAGGAUUUUAUUUCUCCUUCACUUAUGAAGCUUAGUUUGGCUGGAUAUGAAAUUCUGGGUUGAAAAUUCUUUUCUUCAAGAACGUUGAAUAUUGACCCCCACUCUCUUCUGGCUUGUAGAGUUUCUGCUGAGAGAUCAGCUGUUAGUCUGAUGGGCUUCCCUUUGUGGGUAACCCGACCUUUCUCUCUGGCUGCCCUUAACAUUUUUUCCUUCAUUUCAACUUUGGUGAAUCUGACAAUUAUGUGUCUUGGAGUUGCUCUUCUCGAGGAGUAUCUUUGUGGCGUUCUCUGUAUUUCCUGAAUUUGAAUGUUGUCCUCCCUUGCUAGAUUGGGGAAGUUCUCCUGGAUAAUAUCCUGCAGAGUGUUUUCCAGCUUGGUUCCAUUCUCCCCGUCACUUUCAGGUACACCAAUCAGACGUAGAUUUGGUCUUUUCACAUAGUCCCAUAUUUCUUGGAAGCUUUGUUCGUUUCUUUUUACUCUUUUUUCUCUUAACUUCUCUUCUCACUUCAUUUCAUUCAUCUGAUCUUCAAUCACUGAUAACCUUUCUUCCAGUUGAUCGAAUUGGCUACUGAAGCUUGUGCAUUCGUCACGUAGUUCUCAUGCCAUGGUUUUCAGCUCCAUCAGGUCAUUUAAGGACUUCUCUAUGCUGGUUAUUCUAGUUAGCCAUUUGUCUAAUCUUUUUUCAAGGUUUUUAGGUUCUUUGUGAUGGGUUCGAACUUCCUCUUUUAGCUUGGAGAAGUUUGAUCAUCUGAAGCCUUCUUCUCUCAACUCGUCAAAGUCAUUCUCCGUCCAGCUUUGUUCUGUUGCUGGCAAGGAGCUAUGUUCCUUUGGAGGGGGAGAGGCGCUCUGAUUUUUAGAAUUUUCAGCUUUUCUGCUCUGUUUUUUCCCCAUCUUUGUGGUUUUAUCUACCUUUGGUCUUUGGUGAUGGUGAUGUGCAGAUGGGGUUUUGGUGUGGAUGUCCUUUCUGUUUGUUAGUUUUCCUUCUAACAGUCAGGACCGCCAGCUGCAGGUCUGUUGGAGUUUGCUGGACGUCCACGCCAGACCCUGUUUGCCUGGGUAUCACAGUGGAGGCUGUAGAACAGCGAAUAUUGCUGAACAGCAAAUGUUGCUGCCUGAUCAUUCCUCUGGAAGCUUCAUCUCAGAGGGGUACCCGGCCAUGUGGGGUGUCAGUCUGCCCCUACUUGGGGGUGCCUCCCAGUUAGGCUACUCGGGGGUCAGGGACUCACUUGAGGAGGCAGUCUCUCCGUUCUCAGAUCUCAAACUCUGUGCUGGGAGAACCACUGGUCUCUUCAAAGCUGUCAGACAGGGACAUUGAAGUCUGCAGAGAUUUCUGCUGCCUUUUGUUCGGCUAUGCCAUGCCCCCAGAGGUGGAGUCUACAGAGGCAGGCAGGCAGGCCUCCUUGAGCUGCAGUGGGCUCCACCUAGUUCGAGCUUCCCGGCUGCUUUAUUUACCUACUGAAGCCUCAGCAAUGGUGGGCUCCCCUCCCCUAGCCUCACUGCCACCUUGCAGUUCGAUCUCAGACUGCUGUGCUAGCAAUGAGCAAGGCUCCAUGGGCGUGGGACCCUCCGAGCUAGGCACAGGAUAUAAUCUCCUGGUGUGCCGUUUGCUAAGACCAUUGGAAAAACGCAGUAUUAGGGUGGGAGUGACCCAAUUUUCCAGGUGCCGUCUGUCACAGCUUCCCUUGGCUAGGAAAGGGAAUUCCCUGACCCCUUGCCUUCCCGGGUGAGGCCAUGCCUUGCCCUGCUUCAGCUCAUGCUCAGUGGGCUGCACCCACCGUCCUACACCCACUGUCCAACAAGCCCCAGUGAGAUGAACCUGGUACCUCAGUUGGAAGUGCAGAAAUCACCUGUCUUCUGCGUCGCUCACGCUGGGAGCUGUAGACUGGAGCUGUUCCUAUUCGGCCAUCUUGGAACCCAACCCAAGUCUGGCAUUUUUUGGUUUUCUCUGUGUAUUGACUAUGAUUAUAGAGGAUAAAUGGAUAUUGAUAUUAUUAAAUCGUCAUUUACAGAAGGCACACAACUUAUAUCCUUUAAACAAAGUUCUCCAACCAGUAGGGUAUACUUGCUGGUAGUGCUUACAGCUGCCACCAUUCUUCACUGGGGCUCAGAGUGGAUGCCUGGAGGAAAAAAACAAAUGAAUCUUUUAGCUCCUAGUUACUGUUAGCAUUUUUACCAGAAAACAAUUUAAAAAAUGACACAAGUAAGUCUUCACCUAUCAAGGCUGAGUGUGGUGGCCUAUACUUGUAAUCUCUGUGCUUUGGGAGGCCAACGCAGGAGGAUCUCUUGAGUCCAGGAGUUUGAGACCAGCCUGGGCAACAAAGCAAGACCCCAUCUCUACAGAAAGUUAAAAUUUAGCUGGGCAUGCUGGCACAUCCCUAUAGUCCCAGCUACUUGAGAGGCUGAGUUGGGAGGAUCCCUUGAGGUCAUGAGUUGGAGUCUACAGUGAGCUGUGAUUACAGUGUGAGUCUACACUGCACUCCAGUCUGGGUGAAAGAGAUCCUGUCUCUCAAAAAACAAGUGAUUCUCCUGGGAAGAGAUUUGUUUAAAAAGUCUGCACCUCUAUUGAUGAUAACUUUGAAUGUAAAUGGAUUAAAUUCUCCCACUUAAAAGAUAUAGAUUGACUGAAUGGAUUAAAAACCACCAUCAUGACUCGACUGUAUGCUGCCUACAAGAAACCUCACCUGUAAAGACAGGCCAAAAGUGAAGGUAUGGAGAAAGAUAUUGCAUACAAAUGGAAGCCAAAAAAGAGCAGAAAUAACUAUACUUACAUGAGAUAAAAUAGACUUUAAGUCAAAAACUGUAAAAAGAAAAGUCAUUAUGUAAUGAAACAAGGAUCAAUUCAUGCAAGAUAUAAUCAUAUUUUUUUAUUAAGAAAAUUUUUUUGUAGAGAUGGGGUUAUGCUAUGUUGCCUGGCUAGUCUCAAACUCUGGGUCUCAAAGCAGUCCUCCUGCUUUGGCCUCCUAAGGUGCUGGGAUUAUAGGCAUGAGCCACUGUGCCAGGCCUGAGGAUAUUAUCAUUAUAAAUAUAUAUGUACCCCACACUGGAUGACCCAGAUAUAAAGCAAAUAUUAUUAGAUUUAAAGGGAGAAAUAGACUCUAAUACAAUAGUAGUUGAGGACUUCACUCUACUCUCAGCAUUGGACAGAUUUUCUAGACAUAAAACCAAUAAAUAUUGGAUUUAAAUUGCACUUUACACCAAAUGGACCUGACAUUUACAGAACAUUCUAAUAGGUGCAGAACACUCUAAUAGCUGCAGAACACACGUUCUUUUCAUCAGCACAUGGAACAUUCACCAGACUAGUUCUGGAACCCACUUCCUGCCUUAGUGUUCUUUCCACCACAGUGCAUGAUAAUUCCGACAGAACGCCUUUUAUUUGUACCUUAUUAGUUGUAGGGGGAAAGCUUUUUCAUGUACAAAAAUGCUGUAAUUUUCUGAUUUAAUAAAGUAAUUCCACUGA